AGAAUCCAGACGCUAAGGAAAAUCCCUAAGCAGAGAUUUUCUGUUGGAUGCUAAAAGCAAGGAAUAAAAGUUGAAAAUUUGGAAAAUGUCUCAACACCGUCACCAGCGCCACUCGAGAGUCAUUUCUAGUUCACCAGUUGACACUACAUCGGUGGGAUUUUGCCCAACAUUCAAGAAAUUUAAGAGGAACGAUGAUGAAUGUCGGGCAUUUGUGAAGAGAGUCAUAAUGAGCCGUUUCUUUAAGAUAAUUAUGAUUAGCACUGUCACAUCGAAUGCGUUUUUUAUGGCCUUGUGGACCAGUUAUGACAUAAGGUACCGCUUGUUCAGACUUCUUGAGUUCUCGGAGAUCUUCUUUGUGUCCAUCUGCACAUCUGAGUUGUCCAUGAAGGUCUAUGUGGACCCCAUCAACUACUGGAAGAACGGCUACAACCUGCUGGAUGUGAUCAUUAUCAUCGUUAUGUUUUUACCCUAUGCCCUCCGCCAGCUCAUGGGCAAACAGUUCACUUACCUGUAUAUCGCUGAUGGCAUGCAGUCCCUGCGCAUCCUCAAGCUUAUCGGCUAUAGCCAGGGCAUCCGGACGCUGAUCACCGCCGUGGGGCAGACAGUCUACACCGUGGCCUCUGUGCUCCUCCUGCUCUUCCUCCUCAUGUACAUCUUCGCUAUCUUGGGCUUCUGCCUGUUUGGAUCUCCAGACAAUGGUGACCAUGAUAACUGGGGGAACCUGGCUGCAGCUUUUUUCACCCUCUUCAGCUUGGCCACGGUUGAUGGCUGGACAGACCUGCAGAAGCAGUUGGACAAUCGGGAAUUUGCUUUGAGCCGGGCAUUCACCAUCAUCUUCAUCUUGCUCGCCUCUUUCAUCUUCCUCAACAUGUUCGUGGGUGUGAUGAUCAUGCACACAGAGGACUCCAUCAGAAAGUUUGAGCGAGAGCUGAUGUUGGAGCAGCAGGAGAUGCUCAUGGGAGAGAAGCAGGUGAUUCUGCAGCGGCAGCAGGAGGAGAUCAGCAGGCUGAUGCACAUACAGAAAAAUGCUGACUGCACAAGUUUCAGUGAGCUGGUGGAGAACUUUAAGAAGACCUUGAGCCACACUGACCCAAUGGUCUUGGAUGAUUUUGGCACUAGCUUACCCUUCAUCGAUAUCUACUUUUCCACUCUGGACUACCAGGACACAACUGUCCACAAGCUUCAAGAGCUGUACUAUGAGAUCGUGCAUGUGCUGAGCCUAAUGCUGGAAGACUUGCCCCAGGAGAAGCCCCAGUCCUUGGAAAAGGUGGAUGAGAAGUAGCUGGGCAUGGGGCACCCAUGUGCCGAGAGCCUUGCAGACCAUGACAGGUCCCUAUUAAACACAGGCUUUCUGA